ACUCUCCCUUCUCCGGCGUUUCUUCUCCUCCCUCCCCCGCUGCGCCCGCUCCCCCUUCUCCCCUCCAGCGGCCGCCUGGUUUCUGGAAAUCAGGACGCCGCGGCCGGGAGUGGAAGCCAGACCCCAGAUGGAAGGUGCCUGGAGAGGACCCUGCGGACUCGGGGUCGGAGCCCCGGCCUGGGACGGUGACCCCGGGCCUUCCGCCGCUGGCGCCACGCUCAGCCCUUGGCGGUGCCGCUGAGUGGGUCACCACGGGUUCGCCUCCCCAUUGGCCGGUGACGGAGCUCCUUGGGGCUACAGGGCCAGCCAGCCCUUGAUCUCUGGGUUCAGAGGGUGGUACAUGGUGUUACAACCCAGUCUGCGAGGAACGAGUAAAUGAGGAACAAACGCAAAUGAGUAAAUGAGGAACAAACGCAUCUGGCACCUCACUCAGCAGCCCCGAGGCAGGGCUGACCCGCCUCUCCAAGGCCUGCGUCUUUGUGUCCACAGCACUGAAGUUGUUCUGAGUAAAAUCUGCUGCUGGAAAGAAGGGCAAGGAAACACGGGGCCAGAAAGGGUGCCUCGUACAGCAGCAGGAAAAAAUAAAGAUCCUUCUAAACGUAUUUUUAACAUCUUUGAGUCAAGGACAUCAGCGGUCCCGUCACAAAAGAAGAUGCUUGAACGAUCAAUAAACUCAGCCCCCGGAAUUAGGGGAACGCUGUGGGAACAAGAGGAUGCGUUUCACCCUCAUCCUAUCAGAAAACCCCAAGGGUCAAACAACUUAAAGAAUGUUAAUGAAAACGUGGGAAUCUGCAUUCACCGCUGGGAUCACGCAUGGUGCCACCACUUUGAAAGCAACCUUUAGGAAAAUUGAAGCAAGUAGAUGACAAGCCAGAAAGAAAGCAUAUCUCUUUCUAGAUAUGCCCAAGAACACAAACAUAGAUCUGCUCCUUCGAGCCAGGAGCCGUGGUUCUCAACCCCGGCUGUCGUUAAAGUCAUCCAGGAAUGUCUUUAAAAGAAAAAACAUUUCUGCAGCACUGAACCCAGACCAGAUCAAUUGAACCAGAACUUCUGGGAACAAACUAAUAGCUAAGAAUUCCCUAGUCAUUCUAAUAGGCCAUCCACUGUGAGAGAGAAACUACCACAAGAAGUAUGCAUGUGCUAGAAGAUGCGUACAGAAUAUUCCUCACAACACUGUGUGUCCAAAGCACCGGACACACCCUGAAUAUCCAACACGGGGAGAAGCGAUAAAGAAAUGGGCAUAUACAGCGAAAUACCACAUGGCAGUUAAAAUAAAUGAGAGCUACAUGGAUCAAUGUGGAUAAAUGCCAAAAACAGAACGCGGAGCAAAAAUGCAAGUGCACAGUACGGCAGCGAGUACGACAGCAAGUACGGCAGCGAGUAUGGUACCAUUUAUAUAAAGUUUUAAACCAUGAAAAUUAACACUGUUCACUCAGUGAGCCUCUCAAGACUUACUAAACAUCCGCGAUAUACCAGACACUGUUCCAGCAGAUAUUUCGCAGCUAUUUGGGCAGCUUGGAAUGGGAACUGGUGGUCUUCCUAGACCACAGGUAAUGAGGGGUGGCGUGGAGGAGGCAGCCGUGCCAGGCAGGAAGAUCAUCCUGGGAUCUGCGAUGUGUGCAUCGGAAGCACCCAGAGAGAAUAGAAGCUGCCAGAAAAAUGCAAGGAAACCCAGAAACUCGGAGAGCACAAACGAAUCACAGUUUUUAUUGUGUGAAUUUUCACUAAAUAUCCUACAAUGAAUAUUCGUCAUAAGAAAAAGUCAUUUUUAAUGUCAUGAUUUCCUGGAAAUAUAGAAAGAAAGAAAAACAGAAAAGGCACAACUGCCCCCGAGCACAGCAGCAGAAUCUUGGUGGUGGGCGCUCCCCUGCCACGCCCGGGGAUGCUCCUGCUUCAGGAGUUCACUUGGCUCAGUUAUGGCAGCAGGUUCUGAUGCUGCAGAGCUCAGAGCAGAAAGGCUAAGGACGCCUGCUUAGGGCCCCUACUGUGUGUGUGCAUGUCUGUGUGCACGCAUGUGUAUGUGUAGGUCUGUGUGCAGGGCUGUGUGCAUGACUGCACGUAUGUGGAUGGGUGCACAUGACUGUGUACCUGUGUGUGUAUAUGUGUGGGUGGGUGCGCCUGAUUGUGUGUGUGUGUGCGUGUGUGUCUCACGCCAGAUUGGUUCUGCUCAGGUGCUCUGCAUCAUUUCUGCAAUCUGAUUUCUCCAAGUCUCAAAGGUCGAAUGUGCACCAUCAACAGCACUGAGAGCCUCUUAGAAAGGCAAAGUCUCCCCAGACCGGAUGCACUCCCAGCUUCCGUGCCUGGAAUUAGCGUAUUUCCUGCAACACCAGGCCGGGCAGAGCUAGGCAAAGUCACCCAGGAUCUGGAGUUGCCAGAAUGCAGCUUCGGCCACUGACAGCAUCAUCAUGGCCACAUAAAAAAUCCCCCAAAUAAAUUUCCUUGGAAGAAGUAAAUAAGUUCUUUGUACUUAAGUUUGGAGGUGACCAGUCCUAACUGGUAACUGAAUUCCUUGUGAUGUCUUACAAAUCCUUUGCUUUCUAAUUCUAUAAAUUAUGUGUGCUUUUCCCCGGAGAUCUUCUGAGAAUUUCCUUUAGAGAGCAUUUGACUCGGAGGCCAUCGGCAUCAGAUCAGCCCAGGACACUUCAAUGGUGAAUUGUGUGAUAAGCAACAAAAUCUCAGUAAAGCUAAAACAUCAGCACAGAAAAGACCUUAAAGAAACCGCCUCCUCAGCCACAGAGGCGGCACAACGGGAAAGAAACCACCUCCUCGGCCACAGAGCCGGCAGAACCAGAAAGAAACCGCCUCCUCAGCCACGGAGCCGGCACAACGGGAAAGAAACCACCUCCUCGGCCACAGAGCCGGCGCGGCCGGAAAGAAACCGCCUCCUCAGCCAUGGAGCCGGCGCGGCCGGAAAGAAACCGCCUCCUCAGCCACGGAGCCGGCAGAACCCGAAAGAAACCGCCUCCUCAGCCACGGAGCCGGCAGAACCCGAAAGAAACCGCCUCCUCAGCCAUGGAGCCGGCGCGGCCGGAAAGAAACCGCCUCCUCAGCCAUGGAGCCGGCGCGGCCGGAAAGAAACCGCCUCCUCAGCCAUGGAGCCGGCGCGGCCGGAAAGAAACCGCCUCCUCAGCCACGGAGCCGGCAGAACCCGAAAGAAACUGCCUCCUCAGCCACGGAGCCGGCGCGGCCGGAAAGAAACCGCCUCCUCAGCCACGGAGCCAGCGCGGCCGGAAAGAAACCGCCUCCUCAGCCACGGAGCCGGCAGAACCCGAAAGAAACCGCCUCCUCGGCCACGGAGCCAGCGCGGCCGGAAAGAAACCGCCUCCUCAGCCACGGAGCCGGCAGAACCCGAAAGAAACCGCCUCCUCGGCCACGGAGCCGGCAGAACCCGAAAGAAACCGCCUCCUCGGCCACGGAGCCGGCAGAACCCGAAAGAAACCGCCUCCUCAGCCACGGAGCCAGCGCGGCCGGAAAGAAACCGCCUCCUCAGCCACGGAGCCGGCAGAACCCGAAAGAAACCGCCUCCUCGGCCACGGAGCCGGCAGAACCCGAAAGAAACCGCCUCCUCGGCCACGGAGCCGGCAGAACCCGAAAGAAACCGCCUCCUCGGCCACGGAGCCGGCAGAACCGGAAAGAAACCGCCUCCUCGGCCACGGAGCCGGCACAACGGGAAAGAAACCGCCUCCUCAGCCACGGAGCUGGCACAACUGGAAAGCAACUCUCCGAGCUGAAAAGCAAUGGGUUUGCAAAGAGUGGGAAAACACACAGAAGGCGGGUCAUGCAAAACGUCCUCCCGUGUCUGUAAAUGGCAGUUGCCCGCCACGAUGUCCAGAUGCACCGGGGAGUCUGGCCACGCCAAGGGAGAGACCAGAGAGGGCGACUAGCACAGCGUUCACAUCUGGUGGCUCUGUCCCCCCAGACACUCCGCACCGAAGCCUGGGGCAGAGGAGAAACCUCGUGCCUGCACACAGAAGGUGUCUCCACAAGGAGCCGUCUCUACAGCGUGACUGUGGAAAGCAGGCCUCGGGACCCUGGGACCAGCACCAAGAAUGCCAGACCUGGUUCUCCGAGGCUGCGGCAUUCCUCCCACGUCUGCCUCUAGGGGCCACGCAAGGGAGCUGAGACACGGGAGUUACAGAGCACUCAGCUUCCCCACAAGAACUGGCUCUGGUAAGAGCAGCUAGCAUCAAGGAGGAGGAUUCACGUGUGCACCCACCACUCAGAGACACAGACAUAUGCACACUCGCAGACAUGCACACACACCACAGAGACACAGACAUGCCC